GGUUGAGAGUGUGUGUAAAAGAGGAGGGAACUGGGGUUGUGUCUGCACCUCCAUUUGGGUCGGGUGCGUGUGCAAUUGUGUUUAUGGGGCUGAGCUAAUAUUUGGCCUUGGCAUUUGGGAAGUGUCCUUGCCCAUAGUGGGGGACAGAGCGAUGGAUCCCGUUUGACUGGGGGUGGUGGUGAUAAAACAACACUCAACUUUGCCCAGUGGGUGUGGUCCCUGGGGCCGGUUAGAGAGGGGUAGAGGGAGGUGUUGCUCCCCAAAACCUGUGGCCAGCAGUGGACUGGGGGAGGGGGCAGGAAACCAUUUGCUUUCGUGGACAUGUCCAGCGCUUGUUCUCACGAUGGGACGCGUGUCACCCCGGCCCCACCCCCCAGGGACCGACCAGGGAAGCGUGGACGAGGUCAGCAGGGCCUCAUCCAGUCCGCAGCCCAGUGCGGAGUGGGUACGGGGGGAGCUGCUGUUGCCCCAGGAGACGACUGUGGAGCUGAGCUGUGGAGUGGGGCCACUGCAAGUGAUCCUGGGCCCAGAGCAGGCUGCAGUGCUAAACUGUAGCCUGGGGGCUGCUGCCGCUGGACCCCCCACCAGGGUGACCUGGAGCAAGGAUGGGGACACCCUGCUGGAGCACGACCACUUACACCUGCUGCCCAAUGGUUCCCUGUGGCUGUCCCAGCCACUAGCACCCAAUGGCAGUGACGAGUCAGUCCCUGAGGCUGUGGGGGUCAUUGAAGGCAACUAUUCGUGCCUAGCCCACGGCCCCCUCGGAGUGCUGGCCAGCCAGACUGCUGUCGUCAAGCUUGCCACACUCGCAGACUUCUCUCUGCACCCGGAGUCUCAGACGGUGGAGGAGAACGGGACAGCUCGCUUUGAGUGCCACAUUGAAGGGCUGCCAGCUCCCAUCAUUACUUGGGAGAAGGACCAGGUGACAUUGCCUGAGGAGCCUCGGCUCAUCGUGCUUCCCAACGGCGUCCUUCAGAUCCUGGAUGUUCAGGAGAGUGAUGCAGGCCCCUACCGCUGCGUGGCCACCAACUCAGCUCGCCAGCACUUCAGCCAGGAGGCCCUACUCAGUGUGGCCCACAGAGGGUCCCUGGCGUCCACCAGGGGGCAGGACGUGGUCAUUGUGGCAGCCCCAGAGAACACCACAGUGGUGUCUGGCCAGAGUGUGGUGAUGGAAUGUGUGGCCUCAGCUGACCCCACCCCUUUUGUGUCCUGGGUCCGACAAGAUGGAGACAGCCGGGCUCAGAGAGUCCCAGCAAGAGGAGGAAAUGAGAUUCGGACCAGGGACGGUUGUGUUUGCUUUAUCCGGGUGCAGAGUGUUCCUGAGGUUCGGAGACUGAAGGGAAGGGCAGUCCCUAGCGUCCCCUCCAGCGCGUCUCCCUCUCCUUCCCCAGACGGGAAGCCCAUCUCCACAGAUGUCAUCGUCCUGGGCCGCACCAACCUACUAAUUGCCAACGCGCAGCCCUGGCACUCCGGCGUCUAUGUCUGCCGCGCCAACAAGCCCCGCACGCGCGACUUCGCCACUGCAGCCGCUGAGCUCCGUGUGCUGGCGGCUCCCGCCAUCACUCAGGCGCCCGAGGCGCUGUCGCGGACGCGGGCGAGCACAGCGCGCUUCGUGUGCCGCGCGUCGGGGGAGCCGCGGCCAGCGCUGCGCUGGCUGCACAACGGGGCGCCGCUGCGGCCCAACGGGCGCGUCAAGGUCCAGGGCGGCGGUGGCAGCCUGGUCAUCACACAGAUCGGCCUGCAGGACGCCGGCUACUACCAGUGCGUGGCUGAGAACAGCGCGGGAAUGGCGUGCGCUGCCGCGUCGCUGGCCGUGGUGGUGCGCGAGGGGCUGCCCAGCGCCCCCACGCGGGUCACUGCUACGCCACUGAGCAGCUCCGCUGUGUUGGUGGCCUGGGAGCGGCCCGAGAUGCACAGCGAGCAGAUCAUCGGCUUCUCUCUCCACUACCAGAAGGCACGGGGCAUGGACAAUGUGGAAUACCAGUUUGCAGUGAACAACGACACCACAGAACUACAGGUUCGGGACCUGGAACCCAACACAGAUUAUGAGUUCUACGUGGUGGCCUACUCCCAGCUGGGAGCCAGCCGCACCUCCACCCCAGCACUGGUGCACACACUGGAUGAUGUCCCCAGUGCAGCACCCCAGCUCUCCCUGUCCAGCCCCAACCCUUCGGACAUCAGGGUGGCGUGGCUGCCCCUGCCCCCCAGCCUGAGCAAUGGGCAGGUGGUGAAGUACAAGAUAGAAUACGGUUUGGGAAAGGAAGAUCAGAUUUUCUCUACUGAGGUGCGAGGAAAUGAGACACAGCUUAUGCUGAACUCGCUUCAGCCAAACAAGGUGUAUCGAGUACGGAUUUCGGCUGGUACAGCAGCCGGCUUCGGGGCCCCCUCCCAGUGGAUGCAUCACAGGACGCCCAGUAUGCACAACCAGAGCCAUGUCCCUUUUGCCCCUGCAGAGUUGAAGGUGCAGGCAAAGAUGGAGUCCCUGGUCGUGUCAUGGCAGCCACCCCCUCACCCCACCCAGAUCUCUGGCUACAAACUAUAUUGGCGGGAGGUGGGGGCUGAGGAGGAGGCCAAUGGCGAUCGCCUGCCAGGGGGCCGUGGAGACCAGGCUUGGGAUGUGGGGCCUGUCCGGCUCAAGAAGAAAGUGAAGCAGUAUGAGCUGACCCAGCUAGUCCCUGGCCGGCUGUACGAGGUGAAGCUCGUGGCUUUCAACAAACAUGAGGAUGGCUAUGCAGCAGUGUGGAAGGGCAAGACGGAGAAGGCGCCGGCACCAGACAUGCCUAUCCAGAGGGGACCACCCCUGCCUCCAGCCCACGUCCAUGCGGAAUCAAACAGCUCCACAUCCAUCUGGCUUCGGUGGAAAAAGCCAGAUUUCACCACAGUCAAGAUUGUCAACUACACUGUGCGCUUCAGCCCCUGGGGGCUCAGGAAUGCCUCCCUGGUCACCUAUUACACCAGUUCUGGAGAAGACAUCCUCAUUGGCGGCUUGAAGCCAUUCACCAAAUACGAGUUUGCAGUGCAGUCUCACGGCGUGGACAUGGAUGGGCCUUUCGGCUCUGUGGUGGAGCGCUCCACCCUGCCUGACCGGCCCUCCACACCCCCAUCCGACCUGCGACUGAGCCCCCUGACACCGUCCACGGUUCGGCUGCACUGGUGCCCCCCCACAGAGCCCAACGGGGAGAUCGUGGAGUAUCUGAUCCUGUACAGCAGCAACCACACGCAGCCUGAGCACCAGUGGACCUUGCUCACCACGCAGGGAAACAUCUUCAGUGCUGAGGUCCAUGGCCUGGAGAGCGACACUCGGUACUUCUUCAAGAUGGGGGCGCGCACAGAGGUGGGACCUGGGCCUUUCUCCCGCCUGCAGGAUGUGAUCACGCUCCAGGAGAAGCUGUCAGACUCGCUGGACAUGCACUCAGUCACGGGCAUCAUCGUGGGUGUCUGCCUGGGCCUCCUCUGCCUCCUGGCCUGCAUGUGUGCUGGCCUGCGCCGCAGCCCCCACAGGGAAUCCCUCCCAGGCCUGUCCUCCACCGCCACCCCCGGGAAUCCCGCGCUGUACUCCAGAGCUCGGCUUGGCCCCCCCAGCCCCCCAGCUGCCCAUGAAUUGGAGUCCCUUGUGCACCCCCAUCCCCAGGACUGGUCCCCGCCACCCUCAGACGUGGAGGACAGGGCUGAAGUGCACAGCCUUAUGGGUGGCGGUGUUUCUGAAGGCCGGAGUCACUCCAAAAGAAAGAUCUCCUGGGCUCAACCAAGCGGGCUGAGCUGGGCUGGUUCCUGGGCAGGCUGUGAGCUGCCCCAGGCAGGCCCCCGGCCGGCUCUGACCCGGGCCCUGCUGCCCCCUGCUGGAACUGGGCAGACGCUGUUGCUGCAGGCUCUGGUGUACGACGCCAUAAAGGGCAAUGGGAGGAAGAAGUCACCCCCAGCCUGCAGGAACCAGGUGGAGGCUGAAGUCAUUGUCCACUCUGACUUUAGUGCAUCUAACGGGAACCCUGACCUCCAUCUCCAAGACCUGGAGCCUGAGGACCCCCUGCCUCCAGAGGCUCCUGAUCUCAUCUCGGGUGUUGGGGAUCCAGGGCAGGGGGCAGCCUGGCUGGACAGGGAGUUGGGAGGGUGUGAGCUGGCAGCCCCCGGGCCAGACAGACUUACCUGCUUGCCAGAGGCAGCCAGUGCUUCCUGCUCCUACCCGGACCUCCAGCCAGGCGAGGUGCUAGAGGAGACCCCUGGAGAUAGCUGCCAGCUCAAAUCCCCCUGCCCUCUAGGAGCCAGCCCAGGCCUGCCCAGAUCCCCGGUCUCCUCCUCUGCCUAGCUCUUCCCAGAGGAUGUGGUUUGGGGCAGGCAGGUAUGGAUCACAUAGGAUGCGAUACCUGUGGCCGUGUAUGUCCACAUGUGUGCCUGUAGAUACAUCAUCAAGCCCUUUGGAGCUUCCUAAGUUGCUUUGGCUGAGGGGAGAGGAAAACAUGGAUUAUUCACUCCCCCCAUACUCUUUGUGAUACACAUGUGACAUGUGAAAGACAUACGAGACAUAGCUACAUGUGAUGUGCACAUGUGUGAAGUGCAUGUAUGCGUACUGGUUGUUGAGCUGGGAAACCGUGGCCCAGGCAGUGGUCACUACAGCCUGAUUGGUCCUCCAGGUCAGAACGGUGCCCCACAGUGGUCAGUCCCCAGCCCUGUGGGCCCCCACCUCCAUCGCCCAGCCUUUUAUUACACACUCUGAGAGUGUCUCCAAUGCCUGUCUGACAAAGACAGUCCCAGCCCAUUCUCCUGUCUGGCUGGGUUGGGUGCAAGCAGGCUCUGAAUGCCUGGCAUUUCAGCUGCAUCACCUCCCAGCUCCUUAUUGCCCAAAUAGAGAGGGUGGCCCUGGCUCCCCUCCGAGCAACUCUGCAUUUAAUUUUGUAAUCUGGGAAGUGCCUGGUUUUGAAAAUCCGCUUUCUCUCACUCUUCCCCUCCUUCCUUGCCCCUGGCUGCUCUAGUGUUCUGUCUCCCAGUCACCUCGCUCUCCCAGCACCAGUGCCCUUCUCCUGCUCCCAGAUACUCUUUCCUUUCCUCUCUCCUGUUUUCCUUCCUCUGCUAUCUCUCACACCUCUCCCAGACUAUGUCAUCUUGUUCUCCUGCCUGGGUUCAAACUCUGCAUCCUUCUCUAACAACGUGACUACCUCAUGUCUGCUUCAAGGCCCCCGUGCCCUUCCUGUAUCCGCGGCUGCCGCGCACUCGCCUGCCAUCCUCCUGCCUCCUCUUCACUCAGUGCUUCUGCUUGCCCUGCCCCAGGCAGCCCACCCACGCCCAGUGCGGGUGUGGAGAAGAUCUUCUGGCUUCCCUGCAUCUUGCCUUUGGGAUUGGGAUCCAAGGGUUCUCCAUGGAUGGAUCCAAGUCAUAGAGGGGAAUGUUUGAGACAGGGAAGGGGGCUGUGAUCCAGAGGCUCAGAAUAAAAAGAUGCCCUCCCUUCUAUGCAGGGGGGCAAGUUUACUGGAUGGAGAUGAUUUGGGCCUCUCUUCCAGAAGAAGCUAAAGGAAGAGAAGGGGAGUGAGAGUUCAGGGAGGCCCUUCCCACCCUGUGAGGCUUGACUUGAUCUGGAUUGGGGAUGACAGGAAUCUCACCCUCUGGGGUGCUGGCAAGGAGGUCUUUGCACAGGAAAAGGGGUAGCUCAUUUCAGUUUGUUUUUUCUUUAAAUUGAAUCCUCAAGUCAUUUUCUGUUCACCUGCCGCACAGGGACAAGCUUGACUUCUAUUUUCUGUGUAGUGAAAACAAUGUCAUUUAUUUGGUUUUUCACCUCAGCCCUCUCAUAGGAGCAUAGAAUGUUAGGGUCUUUACUCCCUAAUGAUGUCUGAUUGGCACAUCAAGAGUUAACUCUGCCUUCUGGGCCAAAUUCGAAAUAACCAGUCCAUUUUUCCUUUUUUUUUUUUUUUUUUUUAAAUGGUGGAAUGUCUCUCAGCACAGUUGCGGCUUCCUCAAACCCUGAAAGCAUCUGUGUUUAUUAUACUCGGGUGUCACUCACUGUUGAUGUCUGCACCUACGUUUCCACCUCCUCCCCCUCCUUCAGCCAGCCUAUGAUAACACUAAAGAUUAUUAAUGUUGGUUUUGUAUCUCGUUAAAGACAGAAUUGUCACUUGUAGUAUUUCUGUAGCAUUCAGCGCUGCUGUGGCUAACACCACUGUGUAUGUUUCAUCAUUGCUCUGAAGGUCAAAAGCCUCAUUUUAUUUUGCUGGUUUGAUUUUUUUUUUUUAAAGAAGAAAAAAAAACUGCCCUGAAUUAAAUGGCUGUUUUAACAGUAGGCUCUUAGCAUUAUACCACAUAGUCAUUUUUCAUGUUCUUGUUUAACAGGCACUGAGGUUCUGGUUUAAAUUAAAUAGCUGCAAAUGAGACAAUUUAUAACCCAUUAGGUUGGGUGGAAAAUUGUUUCUCAAAAGCAAAUAAGUAAUAAAUCUGGUAUCUGCCUAUAACUCACAGUUGAUAAGAAAGUGGCCAUUUCUCACUAGCACUAUAUAUGAUUUGGGCUCUGGGUAAUUUGGAAGUGUUAGGUUUGUGUCUUUGUAGCAGUAUUUUUAUUAGAAAAGAAUCUAUUGGCCUUUUACAGGGUAUUAAUCCCUUUGUCACCUACCAUUGAUGCCUUAAGUUUUCUGAGUCUCAAUUAAAAAUCUUCCUUUUCUUGAUGCAUGACAAGUGUAAUCAGUACUUGCUCAUUUAUUUGUCUGUAUUUAGUUUAUGCUGUACUAUUUAAUUAUCCUUCCAGCGUUUUUUUUUUCUCCUUACAAAUAUGAUACUCUUUAGUGUUAAGCUAAGGCAUUGAUUCAUGUAUCUGUCCUUAUAAUGAAUUAAUAAACUAUUUUCCAGAAA